AUCUUGGAUUGCGAACUGGGUCGCUACGCUUCACGCCAGGGGCGGAGUGGCGGCCCUUCUGUUACCCGCCACACACGUCGCCGCUGGGGACUGGGAAAUCAGGGCAUCGGAGAGUGCCACAUUAAUGGGUCUCUGGAACCUGGCGGUGCCGGGUGUUUCUCGUGUUUUCCCCAGGGCGACAGCGGUCGCGGGGGCGUGGCAGCCGGACCUUUCCCUUGCGGACGCGAAGGCGUGAUGCCAUGGCUAGUCCAGGGAAAGAUAACUAUAGAAUGAAAAGUUAUAAGAAUAAAGCCCUAAAUCCUCAAGAGAUGCGUAGACGAAGAGAAGAAGAAGGAAUACAGCUUAGAAAACAAAAAAGAGAAGAACAGUUGUUCAAACGCAGAAAUGUCUAUUUGCCCAGAAAUGAUGAAUCUAUGCUUGAAAGUCCUAUACAGGAUCCAGAUAUUAGUUCCACUGUACCCAUUCCAGAGGAAGAAGUUGUUACUACAGAUAUGGUUCAGAUGAUUUUUUCUAAUAAUGCUGAUCAACAGCUAACAGCAACACAGAAAUUUAGAAAGCUGCUUUCUAAAGAACCUAAUCCACCAAUAGAUCAAGUUAUACAGAAACCAGGAGUUGUACAGAGAUUUGUGAAAUUUCUUGAAAGAAAUGAAAAUUGCACUUUACAAUUUGAAGCUGCAUGGGCAUUAACAAAUAUAGCAUCUGGAACUUUUCUGCAUACCAAGGUAGUGAUUGAAACUGGGGCUGUUCCGAUUUUUAUCAAACUUCUUAAUUCUGAACAUGAAGAUGUUCAGGAACAGGCUGUUUGGGCACUUGGUAAUAUUGCUGGUGACAAUGCAGAAUGCAGAGAUUUUGUUUUGAAUUGUGAAAUACUUCCACCUCUUUUAGAGUUAUUAACAAAUUCAAACAGACUCACAACAACAAGAAAUGCCGUGUGGGCCCUCUCAAAUUUAUGUAGAGGCAAAAACCCUCCUCCAAACUUUAGUAAGGUUUCACCUUGCUUAAAUGUCCUGUCACGACUGUUGUUUAGCAGUGACCCAGAUGUGUUAGCAGACGUGUGUUGGGCCCUUUCUUAUCUCUCCGAUGGACCCAAUGAUAAAAUUCAAGCAGUCAUUGAUUCUGGAGUCUGUCGAAGAUUGGUGGAACUUUUGAUGCACAAUGAUUAUAAAGUUGUAUCACCUGCAUUAAGGGCAGUUGGUAAUAUUGUGACUGGUGAUGAUAUUCAAACACAGGUAAUUUUGAAUUGUUCUGCAUUACCCUGUCUCUUACAUUUAUUGAGUAGCCCAAAGGAGUCAAUUAGAAAAGAAGCCUGCUGGACUGUUUCUAACAUCACUGCUGGAAAUAGAGCUCAGAUUCAGGCUGUUAUAGAUGCAAAUAUUUUUCCUGUUUUGAUUGAGAUUCUUCAGAAAGCAGAGUUUCGUACCAGAAAAGAAGCAGCUUGGGCUAUAACUAAUGCAACAUCAGGAGGUACUCCAGAGCAAAUAAGGUAUUUGGUAGCUUUAGGCUGCAUUAAACCACUUUGUGAUCUUUUGACUGUUAUGGACUCCAAAAUAGUCCAAGUGGCUUUAAAUGGACUUGAAAAUAUUUUACGUCUUGGAGAACAAGAAUCUAAGCAGAAUGGAAUAGGCAUUAAUCCAUACUGUGCUCUCAUUGAAGAAGCAUAUGGUCUGGAUAAAAUUGAGUUUUUGCAAAGCCAUGAAAAUCAGGAAAUUUACCAGAAGGCAUUUGAUCUGAUUGAACAUUACUUUGGUGUAGAAGAAGAUGACCCCAGCAUUGUACCUCAGGUGGAUGAAAACCAACAACAGUUUAUAUUUCAGCAGCAGGAAGCACCAAUGGAUGGAUUUCAACUUUAACUUACUGGAGGAAAAAAAAUUUAUGGCUAAAAAGGGUAGCUUCAGGUAACUCCUCUUUGUUGCCAAUGUAAGAAUGUUUGUUUUUUUACAUAGAACAGUAAAGAGAAUUUGAUGCACUUUUAGAAAGCAAAAUGAAACAAAAAUUUCCAUUCAGAUGCAACCUUUCAUUGUAGUUUGUUGUUGUUUUAGUUUUGUUGUUGUGCCUGUAUUUAUAUCUUCUAUUGUUUGGAUUUUUGUAUCUAUUUGUGAAUAAUUGAAUAUGCAAUUAUUUAGUAAUUUAAGCUUGAAAAGGAGAAUUUUGGUGAAGCAUUACUUAGUAAUUCUGAAUUUUUUCAAGCAUUCUUGGAAACUGCACAUUAGCAGUAAACCUAUUGAUAAUUGCAUUUUGGCAGUAAGUCUUACACAUCUAAUCUCUACUAAAUCUACCUCUAUCUUGAAGCAGAAAUAAAAACAAAAAAGCUUCAGAAGCAUGAAAUAAUGCAAAUGCUAAAUUAGAAUGUGAAAAUAUUUAUUACCUUAAAUUAUACAUAUCACUGUGCUGUAGGUUAUACUUUGCAAAAAAUUGCAACAGAAAACCUAUAAAAUUUAUUUAUAAAACAGAAGAAAUAUUAUACUGAUAAUCCAUUAAAAUGUGGCAAUUGUGAAGGGAGAAGCUGUUUUUCAUGUUGAACACAUUAAAAAGAUUACUUUAUAAAAUGUUUAAAUAUUUCUGUUUUUAACAUAUAAGUGCUAUGUAUAUUAGUAUAUUUUGUAUUUCAACCAAAUAUGCUACCAUUUUUGAAAUAGUGUUUUAUUGUUUUUCACUCAUUGUUUUAAAGAGCAUCAUGACAGAGAUGUCAUCAUGAAUCUAAAGUAGUGCUGCAUAUCUAAAAUAAUAACUAAUUAUUUCUCUGAUUUUUCAGAGCAGUAAUUGAAAAGUUUCAUUUUCUGUAUAAUAGUACUAGUUUAAGUUUAAGUACAAGUACAAGUUUAGGUACUCGAAUGACAAAAUUACCCUGAAGAAAUAACCUUAUUAUGUGUUAAAUUGUAUUAAAUGCAUUUAACAUUUGGAUGCUAAAUGAUAAUGAAAAUUGCUAAAGGUUCUUUAAUAUGGUUCAAAUCUAUAAGACUUUUUUCUUUUAGUAAUACUCAGAGGGUCAUUCUGCUGCUUGUUAUGAAUCAUAGAUUACAUUCAUGUCAGAUUGAUCAAUAUGUAUGUUUUAUGAUUUAACAGCAAAAACCUCUUCAAACGGAAAAUUUGAAAGAAAGGUUUCAAUAGAAAAAUUAUAUAUAUAUUUAUACAUAUAUAUGUGUGUGUGUUACUCUCACAGUUCAACUACUGUUGAACUCAAUCUUUUAAUUUAUAGUUAUACGUAGGCUAUUUAUGUGUCCAAUUGUAUACCUAGAAUACUUACUUAAAACUUAGUUUACAACUCUUUUUAAGAUGAGAACUAAGGCAAUUUUGAUAUGAUUCAUGGUCUAUUCUUUAAAAAAAGAUUUCAUUUAUGAUAGUAUUUGUAAUGUUUCUGCUGGAAAUCAGAGGCACGUUCCAAGAGGAAAAUGUAUAUAGGAGUACUUUUAAAGAAUAUGUCACUUUGUAAAUUACAUAUCAUGAAACUAAGCUUUUGACAAGAUACUUAAAACCUACAGCUGUAAAAUACAGGUUUAAAUGGUGUUCGUAAUGCUGAGUGCAUCUGCCAGCCCUUUUUUAUUAUUAAGUAGAAGAUUGUAUCUGUGCCCCUUUUUUCGUAGUGGAAGGUAUAUAGCCGAGUAUAAAAUGGUUUUCUUUUGCAUUAUCUGUAUUCAAAAAACAGGGUAGUUAUAUUAAAGCUUACCAAAUUGAUGGUGAAUUUAUCAGAUUAACCUUUUUGUGGUGCAGAUGGUUCUAAGUAUCAGGUGACAGGGUAUUCUACUCUUUCUAGUCAAUUAAAAUUGAUAAUGCAGCAUGAUUCAUAAACUAACCAGCUGUGCCUCCUUUUAUUUUGAGGACCCUGUAGUCACUAUAAUAAAUUUCUAAGCCAAAUUUUUCAAACAAGAUAGUUCUUAUAGAAGGAGAAAUAAUAAAUAUGUGUGUGUUGAUGCAUGCACACAGAAUGACCUGUGAAAGGAAACUUAAAUUUUGCCGGUAAAACAAACAUAUCUCUACAGACUGUGAUUAUACUUCAUAAGCAUUUAAAUACAGUUUUAUUUAUUUCCUUAAAUAUAUUACUUGGGUAAUUAAUUUUAGAUUUGAUUGCAAAGAGCACUGUAUAGCAGUUGGGACCAGCUCUUGGCUUGGCUUGGCUUGGCUUAUUGUUAAGAGUUUAUUGGAUCAAGACUAACAAAUAACUUUGUGAUGAAAAUUCUUCAAAAAUAUAGCUACUCUUUUCAAGUAUACCAUUUAAAAUAUUUCAUCAGGCAGAGCCCUGACCAGGAAAAAAAAAAAAAAAGAAAGAAAGAAAAGAAAAAAAUAAAUAAAAUGCUCCAAAAAGUGUUUUCAGUAGUCUUCACUGGCCCUUGUGGGAGGAAAAAUACUUUUUUAACUUGCUUUUCUAAGAUUUGUUAUAUUUAAAUCCAAGAGAAACUAUGCCGAAAAAAAGUGUUAUAAAGAGGAAUGCAUGUAGCAUUAAUGCAAAUAUCAAGAAAAUACUUGAAAGAGUCCUUUUCAUUUAUUUAAUUAAAUUUGGUGUUUUAUUUUGUCUGAAUCUGAAUUUCUCCUAUUUAAUCUAUGCAAUUAUGCUUGUUUUAUAUUUAUAAGCACUUGACUCACUGGGUGUGGUCUUUUUACUGUGUUUUAUUUCAAAACGUUGUUUUAAGUGAUAGUGUCCUUAAAUUUUAGUGUCAUUUGGUCAACUUACUGGUAACACCAGAACAAGAAAGCAAAAAAGUAAUAAAUUCUGCUGGCACAGAACUAACAUAUCAUUUGGUAACUGUAAAACCUAUUUGCAGUUAAAGGUUGAUUUAUUGGAUAAGGGACUAAAAGAAGCAUAUAUUACCUUUGCCUUUAUAUUUUUUCUUCUUUUAAGAAGGAGCAUUAUGGAAAAAUAAAUAUAAAGUCUUAGUGAAUUUUUGUUAUGGUUCUCAAUUCAGCAAUCUACUGGCUGCUUGCGAAACUGUGAAAUCAAAUUGUUCUUAACCUUUAUUCAGUUUAGUUUAUAGCAUUACUGUUUUAUGAAAUGUGACAUUUUAGGAGCCAAUAUAAUAGAGCUCUAAAAGGAUAGUAUAUCUUUAAAUUCUGACUGGGGAGUAAGAAGAGAAGAUAUUCUUACCCUACUAAAUAAACCAACUUUUGAGUAGUAUGCAAUAUUAUGAAAUGUUACAACACUAUAUUAAAAAUAAUAAAAUAUUUUAAAAUUGCAUUUAUAUAAAUGUGUCCAUUUCAUUUUUUCUUAAGAUUGUUGUUUCCUAACAGAACAAAGACAGAUGCUAUUAUUGGUUAAAAAUCCAUUUACUUUCUAAAACUAACAAAGGAGAAAAAAUAGAAUUAUAAAAAAUAGCUAAUCCAAAACUAGACAGAAAAAGAGAAAAAACAAAUGAAGAUGGAACAAAUAGCAAGAAAGAUCAAACUCAGUUAUAUCAGUAGUCACAGUAAUUACUAAUGAUUUAAACAUGCCAAUUAAAGUGCAGAGGUUAUCAGUUUUAAUAAAAAAGUAAGGCCGUAUUUUGCCUCUAAGAAAAUGUUUUCAAGAAGCAAAUUGGUGAAAAGGGUGGAAAAAAGAUAUACCAUGCUAUCACAAAUCAAAAGUAAGUUGGGGUGGCCAUAUAAUGCAUAUCAAGGUGCAUUUCAGAGCAAGGAAUAUUUAUUGCUGGAGAUAAAGAGGGUCAUUUGAUAAAGGGAUCAAUUCAUGAUAGUCAAAAUGUAGAAACAAAUGUUCAUCAGCCAAUGGAUAAAUAAAAUGUUAUAUUCAUAAAAUGGGAUAUUACUCAGUAAUAAAAUGAAAUAUGGAUAUAUGGUACAACAUGGAUGAACAUUGAAAACAUUAGGCUAAGUGAAAGAAACCAGAUUCCAUUUAUAUGAAGUGUUCGGAAUAGACAAAUCUAUAGAAACAGAAAUAAAUUAGUAUCUAGGACUGGGGAAAGUUGGAAAUGGGAGGUGACUGGGUACAAAGUUUCUUCUUUGAGCAAUAAAAAUAGGAUUUUCUAAUAAAUUCAGAGAUGUGCUGCCAUCACCAUAAGCAAAAGUUCACUUUUUUACUGGCACUAGCCAUAUUUCAAGUGCUCAGUAGGGAGUGCAGGGCUACAGUAUGUUUUUUAAAUCACGUGAGAGUAACACAAAGUUUUAAAUGCAUAUUUUACACCCCAAAGCAACCAAUUCUUGUUCUUGGAGUUAGCUGAGCUUCCUAGGAUCCAUGGAUUUAUAGUUUUCAUCAAAUUUGAAAACACAGCAAUUAUUUAAACAUUUUUUCAUUUCCAAUUCCGCUUAUAUUAGUCUGCCUGAAAUACUCACACAGCUUAUUAAUGCUUUGCUCAUUUUUGGUUAUUUUUCAUUUUGUAUAGUUUUCAUUGUUUCGUCUUCAAGUUCACUAAUCUUGUCUUCUGCUGUGUCUAAUCUCUUAAUUCCAUUAGUGUAUUUUUUAUGUCAGACAUUGUGUAUUUUAUCUUUAAAAAUUCAAUUUGGAUCUGUUUUAUAUCUUCCAUUUUUUUUAUCAUACUCAAGCUUUCCUCUGCUGGCUUGAACACAGCAAGUAUAAUAGCUGUUUGAAUGGCCUUGCUACUAAUUCUGUCAUUUCUUGCUCUGUUUCUGUUUAUUGAUUUUUUUAUUAUGAGUUGUAUUUUUCAUUUGCAUGCGUUUACAUGUUUGGAUAUUGAAUUUCCCAUAUUUGUUCUUCUUAACACAAGUUACUAGGGGAAAAAAUGUGAUCCUUUAAAGGCUUGCUUUUAAACUUUGUAAGGCAGGCACAGAACAACGUUUAUUUUACUGCUGAGUCAGUACCAUUCCGAGUACUCUAUUACCCUAUGAAUUACAAGGGAUUUUCACUUUGGCUAGUGGAACUUAAACUGUUCCUGAUCAUUGUGGGCUCCAAAAAUUGUUUCCCCUUGUGCUUUCAGGUGAUUCUUUAGAAGGCCUUGGGUAGUAGUCACAUGUGGUCAAUAGUACUUGGCUGAAGACUCAAAGGGGAAUCCUCUGCAGAUAAUCUGGAGCAAUCUGUGUAGUUUUGUCACAUUUGGUACUCUACCUUGUGAACUCUAGUUUUGUCCUCCCUGGCUUCCUAACUCUUUCUCCCCAUCUCAGAGACUUUGUGGCUAUACCUGAAUUUCCCUUCCUUGCCCUGCAAUCGUGAAACUCUAGGCAGUAAGAGACAGAGCAGUCAUAGGGCUCAACUAGUUUGUUUCCUCUGUUUCAUAGAUCACGGUUCCUCAUUAUCUGAUGUCUAAUGUCUGGAAACUGUUGUUUCAUGUUUUUGUCCUGGUCCCUAUUACUCUAGUUUGGCUUAAAGCAGAAGUUAGCAUACCAAUCUAUGUUCUUUUUAAAAUCUCUGUUUAAUGUGGGCUUUGAUCAUUUUUCAUAUUGUUUUCUUGGUGCCUUUUUGUCUCAAUCACUUUCGCUGAAUUCAGUUAUAGUGAUUAUAGUCUUUUUACUUAUUUCCUUAGUUUUUGCUCAUAAUUUUAGAAUUUCCAAUCUUUUAUUCUCUUUGGAUUUAUUCUUAAGUCUUUCCCUAAUUUCCCUAAACAUUUAAGGUUGUUAAAUGUUUAAUUUGGGAAGGCUAAAAAUUUACCUUGAAGUACCAUUUCAGCUGCAUUCCACAAGUUAUUCAGCUCUAAGUAUUUUAAAGUUUAUAUUAUGAUUUAUUCGUGACCUAUGAAAAUUGACAGACCGUUAGCAAGACUAAUAAAGAAGAAAAGAGAGAAGAAUCAAAUAGACGCAAUAAAAAAUGAUAAAGGGGAUAUCACCACCGAUCCCACAGAAAUACAAACUACCAUCAGAGAAUACUAUAAACACCUCUACGCAAAUAUACUAGAAAAUCUAGAAGAAAUGGAUAAAUUCCUCGACACAUAAACCCUCCCAAGACUAAACCAGGAAGAAGUUGAAUCUCUGAAUAGACCAAUAACAGGAUCUGAAAUUGUGGCAAUAAUCAAUAGCUUACCAACAAAAAGAGUCCAGGACCAGAUGGAUUCACAGCUGAAUUCUACCAGAGGUACAAGGAGGAACUGGUACCAUUCCUUCUGAAACUAUUCCAAUCAAUAGAAAAAGAGGGAAUCCUCCCUAACUCAUUUUCUGAGGCCAGCAUCAUCCUGAUACCAAAGCUGGGCAGAGACACAACCAAAAAAGAGAAUUUUAGACCAAUAUCCUUGGUGAACAUUGAUGCAAAAAUCCUCAAUAAAAUACUGGCAAACCGAAUCCAGCAGCACAUCAAAAAGCUUAUCCACCAUGAUCAAGUGGGCUUCAUCCCUGGGAUGCAAGGCUGGUUCAAUAUACGCAAAUCAAUAAAUGUAAUCCAGCAUAUAAACAGAACCAAAGACAAAAAACACAUGAUUAUCUCAACAAAUGCAGAAAAGGCCUUCGACAAAAUUCAACAACGCUUCAUGCUAAAAAACUCUCAAUAAAUUAGGUAUUGAUGGGACGUAUCUCCAAAUAAUAAGAGCUAUCUAUGACAAACCCACAGCCAAUAUCAUACUGAAUGGGCAAAAACUGGAAGCAUUCCCUUUGAAAACUGGCACAAGACAGGGAUGCCCUCUCUCACCACUCCUAUUCAACAUAGUGUUGGAAGUUCUGGCCAGGGCAAUUAGGCAGGAGAAGGAAAUAAAGGGUAUUCAAUUAGGAAAAGAGGAAAUCAAAUUGUCCCUGUUUGCAGAUGACAUGAUUGUAUAUCUAGAAAACCCCAUUGUCUAAGCCCAAAAUCUCCUUAAGCUGAUAAGCAACUUCAGCAAAGUCUCAGGAUACAAAAUCAAUGUACAAAAAUCACAAGAAUUCUUAUACACCAAUAACAGACAAACAGCCAAAUCAUGAGUGAACUCCCAUUCACAAUUGCUUCAAAGAGAAUAAAAUACUUAGGAAUCCAACUUACAAGGGACGUGAAGGACCUCUUCAAGGAGAACUACAAACCACUGCUCAAUGAAAUAAAAGAGGAUACAAAGAAAUGGAAGAACAUUCCAUGCUCAUGGGUAGGAAGAAUCAAUAUCGUGAAAAUGGCCAUACUGCCCAAGGUAAUUUAUAGAUUCAAUGCCAUCCCCAUCAAGCUACCAAUGCCUUUCUUCACAGAAUUGCAAAAAACUACUUUAAAGUUCAUAUGGAACCAAAAAAGAGCCCGCAUCGCCAAGUCAAUCCUAAGCCAAAAGAACACAGCUGGAAGCAUCACGCUACCUGACUUCAAACUAUACUAUAAGGCGACAGUAACCAAAACAGCAUGGUACCAGUACCAAAACAGAUAUAGAUCAAUGGAACAGAACAGAGCCAUCAGAAAUAAUGCCGCAUAUCUACAACUAUCUGAUCUUUGACAAACCUGAGAAAAACAAGCAAUGGGGAAAGGAUUCCCUAUUUAAUAAAUGGUGCUGGGAAAACUGGCUAGCCAUAUGUAGAAAGCUGAAACUGUAUCCCUUCCUUACACCUUAUACAAAAAUUAAUUCAAGAUGGAUUAAAGACUUAAACAUUAGACCAAAAACCAUAAAAACCCUAGAAGAAAACCUAGGCAUUACCAUUCAGGACAUAGGGAUGGGCAAGGACUUCAUGUCUAAAACACCAAAAGCAAUGGCAACAAAAGCCAAAAUUGACAAAUGGGAUGUAAUUGAACUAAAGAGCUUCUGCACAGCAAAAGAAACUACCAUCAGAGUGAACAGGCAACCUACAAAAUGGGAGAAAAUUUUCACAACCUACUCAUCUGACAAAGGGCUAAUAUCCAGAAUCUACAAUGAACUCAAACAAAUUUACAAGAAAAAAACAACCCCAUCAAAAAGUGGGUGAAGGACAUGAACAGACACUUCUCAAAAGAAGACAUUUAUGCAGCCAAAAAACACAUGAAAAAAUGCUCACCAUCACUGGCCAUCAGACAAAUGCAAAUCAAAACCACAAUGAGAUACCAUCUCACACCAGUCAGAAUGGCAAUCAUUAAAAAGUCAGGAAACAACAGGUGCUGGAGAGGAUGUGGAGAAAUAGGAACACUUUUACACUGUUGGUGGGACUGUAAACUAGUUCAAGCAUUGUGGAAGUCAGUUUGGCGAUUCCUCAGUGAUCUAGAACUAGAAAUACCAUUUGACCCAGCCAUCCCAUUACUGGGUAUAUACCCAAAGGAAUAUAAAUCAUGCUGCUAUAAAGACACAUGCACACAUAUGUUUAUUGCAGCACUAUUCACGAUAGCAAAGACUUGGAAUCAACCCAAAUGUCCAACAAUGAUAGACUGGAUUAAGAAAAUGUGGCACAUAUACACCAUGGAAUACUAUGCAGCCAUAAAAAAUGAUGAGUUCAUGUCCUUUGUAGGGACAUGGAUGAAAUUGGAAAUCAUCCUUCUCAGUAAGCUAUCGCAAGAACAAAAAACCAAAUGCCGCAUCUUCUCACUCAUAGGUGGGAAUUGAACAAUGAGAACACAUGGACACAGGAAGGGGAACAUCACACUCUGGGGACUGUUGUGGGGUUGGGGGAGGGGGGAGGGAUAGCUUUAGGAGAUAUACCUAAUGCUAAAUGACGAGUUAAUGGGUGCAGCACACCAACAUGGCACAUGUAUACAUAUGUAACUAACCUGCACAUUGUGCACAUGUACCCUGAAACUUAAAGUAUAAUAAAAAAAAAAGAAAUGUACUUUUAAAUUUCAGACCUUAAAAAUAUGCCACUAACUUCUAAGUUGUGAUGUGAUUACAUGAGUUUGAAAUUCGUUGAUACUUGCUUUAUGAUCUGAUAUGUGUUGGUUUUAGUGAAAUGGCCCAUGUGUGUAAGAAAAGAAUGUGUUUUGUUAAUUGAUUCAUGUCUUUUACAUACUAGUCUGCUUAAUUCAUCAGUUUCUAACUCGCCAGUUUCUAAGAGAGGUGUGUUAAAAUCUCCCAAGAUGAUUGGUGGAUUUUGAAUUUUCCAUAUAGUUCUGACGAUUUUUUUGUGUUUUAUAUGUUUUUUACAUUAUUUUGUGCAUAGAAAUUUAGAAUUACAUCUUUUUUUUUAAGGUUCAGAUGAGAAUUUGUACAUUUAUGUGCUAAAAGUACAGAACAAUAGUUGACAUUUUCAGAGUACUUGUUAAGUGAAUUUUAACAAAAUAGUUGAAACUUAUUUGAAAAUAUUUUCCCUUUGGUCUUUGUGGUAGAAAUGACAGACUUUUUCAUUGAAUGAUGAGGACACAGCAGCCAUAUUAUGCCAAGAGGAAAAAUAUCAUGAUCAUAUUGAAAGAUCAAGCAUGAGCUUCCAUGGUGAAGUCUUCUGUACCAAUGCACCAGAGAAUGCCUACCAUCCAAAAAAGCAGUCAGCUGAUGGAAAAGAAGAUUAUUAAACCUUUGUUCUGGGAUUUACUGUUAAAAAACAAACAAAAAACAACAAAAAAGCGGUGACAGGAAACAGUUAAGGAAAUGAUUUAACUGAAGGGAAGCAAGAUUUUUUUAAAGCAUUGUUCUUAAUCCCCAUGACUGUCCUUCAGUCACAAUUCCAGAAUAAAAGAAUCUACUUUGUGUA